GCAUUCCAGAGCCAGCAGCGCGUCCUGGCCGCUCCUGCGCUCUCCCGCCUCCCGGGGCUCGGAGGAGCCGGGGCACGUUCCAGGAGCUGCCUAGGGCUGAGGUUCCAGGCCUGGGGGUCGCUUCCAGCUGCCAGAUCCCGUGCAGUCCUGGGGACCCUGAGAAGCACCGAGCCAUCCCUGACCCAGGAACUUUCCGCAGACUCGCCGCCAUCUGGGAGUGAAGCAACAUGGAUGCAGUCAGCCAAGUCCCCAUGGAAGUCGUGCUUCCCAAGCACAUCCUGGAUAUCUGGGUUAUUGUCCUCAUCAUCCUGGCCACCAUUGUCAUCAUGACCUCGUUGUUGCUGUGCCCAGCCACUGCAGUAAUCAUCUAUCGCAUGCGGACUCAUCCGAUCCUUAGUGGGGCUGUUUGAGAGCCUCCCAAGAGGGCCGGGUGAGGGAUGAGGACAGGCAUCCUAUCCCCAGCCUCUUCCUGUCUUCAGAAAAGCAGCAGGAGGGACUUUGGGGCAUGGACCUGAGUUCUGGUUUUGAUUCUGCCACGAGCCAGCUGUGUGAAUUUGGUCAAGGGACCUAACUCUCUGAGUUCCAGGUUCCUUAUCUUUCAAAUGGGGAUGGUGAUCCCUGCCCUUUCUACCUCAUAGGGAUGUGAGAACCACCUGACUUAGUGGAUGUGAAAGCUGUUUGUGAUCAGUAAAGCUACCACAGAUAUAAGGGUGUUAUGCUGAAUCCUGAGAAGCUUUCAAGAACCAGAGAACCUGAUUGCUGAUGAUGGCCUUAAAGGUGGUGAGGGAGAUACUGGGGGCAGAGCAGACUUUGCCAGUGCCCCUCAGGUCAAACCAAGCCAAGAGCACCCUGUCCCCAUUCCAAGGGGCCAGCAGCACUUUGGCCCAAAGUAUUUUCUUUAAGGUGCCAUUCCUUCAUGUUUUCUCAGUUUGGAGGGUGAUGGGUAGAGCUUUCCAGAACCUUCUCCAUUCCAGAAUCUCUGCCCCUGUGUAAUCUGAAGGAAGGCUGUGCCAUCUUUGGGCACUGCCAAGGGAGUUGGGGUGAUGGGCUUCUUUCUGCACUGGAGUCUCACAUCUGUUAGCUUUGACACUCAAGCAAUGUUGGAAAAUGCAGGGUGACUGAGUUCCCUGCCCAGCUUUCGGGAUCUCUGGCCCCCAUCCCCUUGUGUGUGUCCCUCUGCCCAGCUCCUGCUGUAAUUAGCUCCACGUGUACCCCCUUCACUCCCUCCCACCAGCUCUGCAGCCAGCCUAUGGCAAUUAUAUUUUAAGAGGUGUUCCCAGGACUUUUGGGACCUACUAAAACAAUGAUGGUUAUUUUAGAUGUGAUGAUUUAUAUUUAUGUAGAGAUAUUUCUGGACCACUCAAGCUCUUCGAUACCAAAAUCAGGAGCAUCUUGGGAUUUAUUAAAUUAUGUAAGAAGAUAGCACAGAUAUCGGGAUAUUAUUGUGUGAAAAUGCUGCUUUUACUUUGAUGUGAUCUCAUUGAUGUACACAACCAAGUUCCAAUAAAGUGCUAGAAUGUG